AAGUCUCUACUGAGGAAAGCUAUGAGGAUACUCUGUUCGUAAGCUCCCGGUGAAUUUUGUUCCACAGACUCGGAAGAAAGGUUGGAUAAGAGUUCACUGGAGAUUGACAAGUACUCGGGAUAGUGAAAAGCCGGAGUUGGAACAUGGAUAGCCGCUUGCAGGAGAUCCGGGAGCGGCAGAAGUUACGGCGACAGCUCCUCGCGCAGCAGUUGGGAGCUGAAAGUGCCGACAGCAUUGGUGCCGUGUUAAAUAGCAAAGAUGAGCAGAGAGAAAUUGCUGAAACAAGAGAAACUUGCAGGGCUUCCUAUGAUACCUCUGCUCCAAAUGCAAAACGUAAGUAUCUGGAUGAAGGAGAGACAGAUGAAGACAAAAUGGAAGAAUAUAAGGAUGAACUAGAAAUGCAACAGGAUGAAGAAAAUUUGCCAUAUGAAGAAGAGAUUUACAAAGAUUCUAGUACUUUUCUUAAGGGAACACAGAGCUUAAAUCCCCAUAAUGAUUACUGCCAACAUUUUGUAGACACUGGACAUAGACCUCAGAAUUUCAUCAGGGAUGUAGGUUUAGCUGACAGAUUUGAAGAAUAUCCUAAACUGAGGGAGCUCAUCAGGCUAAAGGAUGAGUUAAUAGCUAAAUCUAACACUCCUCCCAUGUACUUACAAGCCGAUAUAGAAGCCUUUGACAUCAGAGAACUAACACCCAAAUUUGAUGUGAUUCUUCUGGAACCCCCUUUAGAAGAAUAUUACAGAGAAACUGGCAUCACUGCUAAUGAAAAAUGCUGGACUUGGGAUGAUAUUAUGAAGUUAGAAAUUGAUGAGAUUGCAGCACCUCGAUCAUUUAUUUUUCUCUGGUGUGGUUCUGGGGAGGGGUUGGACCUUGGAAGAGUGUGUUUACGAAAAUGGGGUUACAGAAGAUGUGAAGAUAUUUGUUGGAUUAAAACCAAUAAAAACAAUCCUGGGAAGACUAAGACUUUAGAUCCAAAGGCUGUCUUUCAGAGAACAAAGGAACACUGCCUCAUGGGGAUCAAAGGAACUGUGAAGCGUAGCACAGACGGGGACUUCAUUCAUGCUAAUGUUGACAUUGACUUAAUUAUCACAGAAGAACCUGAAAUUGGCAAUAUAGAAAAACCUGUAGAAAUUUUUCAUAUAAUUGAGCAUUUUUGUCUUGGUAGAAGACGCCUUCAUCUAUUUGGAAGAGAUAGUACAAUUCGACCAGGCUGGCUCACAGUUGGACCAACGCUUACAAAUAGCAACUACAAUGCAGAAACAUAUGCAUCCUAUUUCAGUGCUCCUAAUUCCUACUUGACUGGUUGUACAGAAGAAAUUGAGAGACUUCGACCAAAAUCGCCUCCUCCCAAAUCUAAAUCUGACCGAGGAGGUGGAGCUCCCAGAGGUGGAGGAAGAGGUGGAACUUCUGCUGGCCGUGGACGAGAAAGAAAUAGAUCUAACUUCCGAGGAGAAAGAGGUGGCUUUAGAGGGGGCCGUGGAGGAGCACACAGAGGUGGCUUUCCACCUCGAUAAUUGUUGAAGACAUUGAACCUAUUCAUCCUCCUCUAACCUUCUUUAUUGUAAUUAAAUUUCAAGUGGGAGACUUAACUUUAGAACUCACUUCCAGCUUGCACUUUGCUUUAAUUUCUCUGAGCUGCAAGAAUGUCUUAGCGAGCCUUGCUUGCAGUUGUCACACACACUGUCUGGUUUUUUUCAGGAUAAAUGAAUGAUUCUGCCUUUUGUUAUGUGCGUGAACAGAAUGGAACAACUCAAGUAGCUUCAUCUUCAGAGACUGAAUUUAUUCUGAUAGACUUCAGCUAAUUACAAAGGAUUUUGCUAAUUUUUGGGAAUAAAUAAUGGAAAAAGAUCCAGUCUGUGGUAUCAUGCUAGUGCUGACAGGGCCUUGAUAGAAUAGAGUUGGAAAAGAUGGUAAGCUUUUGUCAGGGUUUUAACAUUUUCUUGAUGAAACAAUAAAAAGAGGUAAGCUUUUUUCUUCUUUUUUUUUAAGUUUUAAAUAAACUCAGAUAUAAUUUGAAUACUGAAGAAAUUAAGAGACUUUGAACAAAAACUCUUCCCAAAUCUAAAUUUGAUAGGGGAGGUGGAGAUUCCAGGGGUGGGUGAAAGAAGAGAUAGAACUUAGCAGGCAGACUUAAAAAAAAAAAAAAAGUUUAUCAUCAUAAUCUCAAUUUUGUGGCUAUGACUCCUAAUCACGCUUCCUAAGAAGCAAAGGAGGACAAAUAUUCAUGUGCUAGAUAGCACUGUGGUGUGGACUUGAACUUGGAUUGACCUUAAAUUUUAUAUUCCUCAAAUAAAAGAGAGGCAGCGACAAGAUACCUCAUUAUCAGAUGCUUGGUUUAUACAUUUUGGGACUAAAAUACUUGGUGAUGAAAUGACAUACACCUUUAAACUUGUUAUGGAGAUAGUUUAAUGUAAAACCAACUACGGAAAACCCUCAACUUAAGGAUACAGCUUGGAAAUUGGAACUGCAAUUGCCUUUUAUUAAAACCAUAUGGUGUGAUGUUUGUUUUUAAAAUUAUAUAAGACUUUAUGCUGUCACUUCUCUUGCUGUACUGUAAUUCAUGUUUUAAAUGAAUUUGAUAAUGAAAUUAUACUAUUAUCAUUCUUGAUGAAUACUUUUCUUAUUUUUAUGAUUUUUCUAAUGAAACUUUAAACUUUUGAGAUUUGAGAGUCUGUUUUCUAUAAGUAGAAUUACUGUUGUUACAAAAUGAAAAAGGACUGACCUAAAAUCAGUCUCUUCUUUUGGUCUGUGAUGGAUUUUAAUGGCCGUUCUGUGCUCAUAUAUACCUAAGAUGAGAUUAUAUUACAUCCACCAAAGACUCAGUUUGAAGAUAAGGAAUGAGUGAUAGAAGAAAUAAGGCUGAGAUCCUUAAAAGCCUAAUUAAUUUAACUCGCUUAACCCAUUAGUACUAUCUAGUACAAGACCCCUUUUUUUUUGCUGAAAUUAUGGUAUAUUUUCAACUUCACUAAUUACAAAUUAUCUAGAUUUAGAACUCUAUAUGUCAGCAUUGACCUGGGAAUGAAGUCAGGAUAGAGAAAUUCCACUUGCCUGUGAUGGGUCCUUAGAAGUAUCAGCUAAGGAGUGACCCUGUCCUAUACACAGGGCUCUCUAUUACGUUCCAUACCCUGGGCCUACCCAAGGUGACAUUCCUGCUGUUUACAUGGCAUAGGCACCUGUGAGAUCAGUGUCACAAUUUCAUCUUAGAAAGAGGUAGGUAUGGCUGCUUUGUCGGUUGAAAGUUAAGGGGAGCCAUGAUCUACCAUAUUUAGGAAAAAGUUAUUUAAAAAAGAGCAGAUGGUGGAAAAAGAAUGUAAGACCCAGAAUUUAUCCCUUUGACAAUGAAUCUGGCCUUUUUAAUAGCAGGAUGGAAUUGAUUCACUAGUUUUUGCUAACUUUCACUUUCAGUAAAGGUUGAGGUGUUGUUUUUGCAAUGACUGUGUAUUCAUUGAGGAAAGGUUUCCAAUGAAAUUUCAUUACUCUGACCUCUUCUAAUUUUUGGUCUUCUUUAUAUUUACAUGUCUUACAUUCCACAAAAUUAUUUAGAAAUGCUGGGCAUGGUGGCUCAUGCCUGUAAUCCCAGCACUUUGUGAGGCCGAUGUGGGUGGAUCACUUGAGGUCAGGAGUUUGAGACCAGCCUGACCAAUAUGGAGAAAUCCCAUCUCUACUAAAAAUACAAAAUUAGCUGGGCGUGGUGGCAUGUGCACGCCUGUAAUCCCCGCUACUCGGGAGGCUGUGGCAGGAGAAUUGCCUGAACCCAGGAGGCGGAGGUUGCAGUGAGCCGAGAUUGUGCCACUGCACUCCAGCCUGGGCGACAGAGUGAGACUCUGUCUCAAAAAAAAAAAAAAAAAUUGUAUAGAAAUAAAUUUUUAGUUGCUUUAUGCACUAAUUCCUUACUGGGGAUAGAAGCUAAUUAUUGUGAAAUAACCUAGUUUAGAAGUUAGAAGAUCAGCAUGUCUGAGUUUUUACAGAAUUAUAAUUCAUGGUAUUCCAAACCAACUGUUGUUAUUUAUUUCCAGUGAGAACCAUUUUCCCACUGACCUUCCUCCUUUCAGAGGAUGGGGAUUAGGAGGCCCAAAGUACUGAUUGAGUAGGAAUACUUUUUUACUCUUCUUCACUGUGGAGAAAGAAGAGGGCAGGUAGUUGAUGAUGUCAGGAGAACAGAUUUUAUGGUGUGGAAUACCAUACCUAAACACAAAUGAAUCAGAUUAGACCACAGAAUUGUGAUGAUGGCAGUCAGAAUGUAAUACGGUCAUCAUGAAACAGCACAGUGUGAGAGGUCAAGGUGUCAACCUGGGAAGUGAGAAUCAAGCAGGAGUGUGGCAUGGCAACCAACUCACAGAUCCAGAGUUGAGAGGGAUCACUACUGCAGCAGUUCUGCUCUGUUACUCUGGUAAGUAGUAGAGCCACUUUAUGAGCCCUUAUUUCCUAUCUCCCUUAUUCUGAGGCCAGGUCAGUGAUAUGCUAUAGUUUCAUUUAAGUUAAUGGAGUAUAAAGAUGGGAUACUUGGGAGCUAUAUUGUGCAUCAGGGUGUCACAGCUGCUACUAGGAGUUACUCCUUUUCAUGUCUUUUAAAAUACUUUCUACCCAUCUUAAUUGCUAAAUUAUCUUUCAGUUAGUUACAGCGCUUAAUUUAAAACCUGUACUGUUUUCAUCCUGAAUUUAGAACAUAAGAUUUAGCCUUUGAAGUAUAGUUUCAGACUUUACUAAUUUGUUUAAUAUAAUCCUUAUUAACAUGACAAAAUGAAAGCCCUGUUGGGACUUAGUCUAAACAGUAGUCUUUGAUCUGAAAGUGUCUCAUAUUUUGUGAUCUAUUAGAAACAUAAACCUUUGCUUAUGCAGAAGGUCUUUCUUAGAACAAUCCUGUAAUCUUAGGGUUCAUGUGUGACUAGCAUUAUCCUCUCUUUGAUGUUGGGUAAUAGAGGCUGAACUUUUCUUGUGUAUAUAUAGUUAGUUUUGAGGCCAUAAAUCUAGGACUUCUCAAAAGAUUAGAACAUUUAUCCAGUAAACUGACUCCAUUGAAGACUUCAUUUCUGGAAAUACCACAUUGCUUCUGCUCUCAAUAACUCUAUCAUUUACUCGUAUAAAUAUUGCUAGCUGUAAUGCACAGAGAAAAACUACCUCAUUCAAUCUAGAUAAUUGGGACAUCCUUUUCCAGUAAACCCUUUUUCCACUACUGGAUAAAAUAUUAAAAUGAUCAGUUUGAGUGUAUGUUAGAGUUCAUGUUUCUGUAACUAAAGGUGCUAAUAAACUGAAAUCAGAUAAGGUAGGUUUUUCCAAAAAUACUUCUAAAUAAUUGACAACCUAGAAGUCAACAAUGUAAAAUGCAUAUGGGACUCUAUAUUAAUAGAGAAGCAGGCCAAGAACUUUUUAAUGGGAUAAUUGUCUUCUUUAGGCACAUUGUUUGCAUAUUAACGACAUGGAAAUAUUUUCACUCAUUUACUUUCAUCCAUCUAUCUGUGCUUUUUCUCACUUUGAUGAGUUCUCUCAACUCCUUUCUAAGAAAAGCAGAGCAGAGCAGCAUAGAGUGCGUUAGUAAAUGGCCACUGACUCUUGGUCUCAGGCCAUAGCAACUAUAGAGAGAAGAGUGGGGCUGGAGACCUCAUACCCUGGGUAAAGUGGACAUCACUUGUCAGCUCCAGCUAAUUGUCACCACAGAGAGAAGAGGGUAAGUCUGAGAUGUUCAUGUGCAUUUCCCUACAUUUUAGAGGUUGACAAAAUAGUUUGUGACUUUUGCUUACAUUUGCAUUCAUAGAACUAAAAAAAAUUUAACUUGGCUAACAAAAUACCACAUGCAUAUUUUCUUUUUUAUUUUUAUUUUUUGAGACAGAGUCUCUGUUACCCAGGCUGGGGGGCAGUGAUAAGAUCUUGGCUCACUGCAACCUCCGCCUCCAGGGUUGAAGCGAUUCUUCUGCCUCAGCCUCCUGAGUAGCUGGAAUUACAGGUGCCCACCACCACACCCAGCUAAUUUUAGUAUUCUUAGUAGAGACAGGAUUUCACCAUGUUGGCCAGGCUGGUCUCAAACUCCCGACCUCAACUGAUCCACCCACCCUGGCCUCCCAAAGUGUCAGGAUUACAGGCGUGAGCCUCUGCAACUGGCCAACAUGCAUAUUUAAAUUAUGCAUGCAUUGUAGCUGUAUACUGUGUGACCACAUUUACUUAAAAAAGAGGAAAAAAGGUUACUUGCUUGAGACAGGAAACUAUCACCUUUGAAAGCAUAUUAAGUAGUUGGCUUACUUUGGAACACACAGUAGACUGAAAAUGUGAACUAAUACUUUAAAAUUGCCGUAUAAUGAUGUCAUUGCAAGCCAUUCAUCUAUCCAAUGGGGGAAAAUGUGGAGGUCUAGGCUUGUGUUGUCACAAAAUACACCUUUUAGAUAAUCCUUACCUGUACAGAUUUUUAUAACUGUUGUUAUCAUAAGAGAAUGGCUACAUCAUUAUCCUGCCUUUUCUGGGUGUUUAUUUUGUUGUUUUUGAAAGUGGACAAAACCUCAAAGCACAAUUUUGUUCUGAUAUAUCCAGUUUAGUAGUUUAUGCUGGUUAAAUGAUCAAAGUAAUUGCUUAAAUGUCUUGUGGAAUUAGCUGUCACUUUAUAGUUUAUGUAUUGUGGUGGGUACCUUAAUAAUAAAAAGAUUUUUAAUGUAA